AUGACCCACUGUUGCUCCCCUGGCUGUCAGCCUACCUGCUGCAGGACCACUUGCUGCAGGACUACCUGCUGGCAGCCCACCAUUGUGACCACCUGCAGCAGCACACCCUGCUGCCAGCCCUCCUGCUGUGUGUCCAGCUGCUGCCAGCCUUGCUGCCACCCAACUUGCUGUCAAAACACCUGCUGCAGGACCACCUGCUGCCAGCCCACCUGUGUGACCAGCUGCUGCCAGCCUUCCUGCUGCAGCACACCCUGCUGCCAGCCCAUCUGCUGUGGGUCCAGCUGCUGUGGCCAAACCAGCUGUGGGUCCAGCUGCUGCCAGCCCAGCUCCUGUGCACCCAUCUACUGCAGGAGAACCUGCUACCACCCCACGAGUGUCUACCUGCCUGGUUGCCUAAACCAGAGCUGUGGCUCCAGCUGCUGCCAGCCGUGCUGCCGCCCAGCCUGCUGUGAGACUACCUGCUGCAGGACCACUUGCUUCCAGCCCACCUGUGUGACCAGCUGCUGUCAGCCUGCUUGCUGCUGA